CUUCCGGAUGAAGGCUAUUUGAAGUCGCCAUAACCUGGUCAGAAGUGUGCCUGUCGGCGGGGAGAGAGGCAAUAUCAAGGUUUUAAAUCUCGGAGAAAUGGCUUUCGUUUGCUUGGCUAUCGGAUGCUUAUAUACCUUUCUGAUAAGCACAACAUUUGGCUGUACUUCAUCUUCAGACACCGAGAUAAAAGUUAACCCUCCUCAGGAUUUUGAGAUAGUGGAUCCCGGAUACUUAGGUUAUCUCUAUUUGCAAUGGCAACCCCCACUGUCUCUGGAUCAUUUUAAGGAAUGCACAGUGGAAUAUGAACUAAAAUACCGAAACAUUGGUAGUGAAACAUGGAAGACCAUCAUUACUAAGAAUCUACAUUACAAAGAUGGGUUUGAUCUUAACAAGGGCAUUGAAGCGAAGAUACACACGCUUUUACCAUGGCAAUGCACAAAUGGAUCAGAAGUUCAAAGUUCCUGGGCAGAAACUACUUAUUGGAUAUCACCACAAGGAAUUCCAGAAACUAAAGUUCAGGAUAUGGAUUGCGUAUAUUACAAUUGGCAAUAUUUACUCUGUUCUUGGAAACCUGGCAUAGGUGUACUUCUUGAUACCAAUUACAACUUGUUUUACUGGUAUGAGGGCUUGGAUCAUGCAUUACAGUGUGUUGAUUACAUCAAGGCUGAUGGACAAAAUAUAGGAUGCAGAUUUCCCUAUUUGGAGGCAUCAGACUAUAAAGAUUUCUAUAUUUGUGUUAAUGGAUCAUCAGAGAACAAGCCUAUCAGAUCCAGUUAUUUCACUUUUCAGCUUCAAAAUAUAGUUAAACCUUUGCCGCCAGUCUAUCUUACUUUUACUCGGGAGAGUUCAUGUGAAAUUAAGCUGAAAUGGAGCAUACCUUUGGGACCUAUUCCAGCAAGGUGUUUUGAUUAUGAAAUUGAGAUCAGAGAAGAUGAUACUACCUUGGUGACUGCUACAGUUGAAAAUGAAACAUACACCUUGAAAACAACAAAUGAAACCCGACAAUUAUGCUUUGUAGUAAGAAGCAAAGUGAAUAUUUAUUGCUCAGAUGACGGAAUUUGGAGUGAGUGGAGUGAUAAACAAUGCUGGGAAGGUGAAGACCUAUCGAAGAAAACUUUGCUACGUUUCUGGCUACCAUUUGGUUUCAUCUUAAUAUUAGUUAUAUUUGUAACCGGUCUGCUUUUGCGUAAGCCAAACACCUACCCAAAAAUGAUUCCAGAAUUUUUCUGUGAUACAUGAAGACUUUCCAUAUCAAGAGACAUGGUAUUGACUCAACAGUUUCCAGUCAUGGCCAAAUGUUCAAUAUGAGUCUCAAUAAACUGAAUUUUUCUUGCGAA